GAUAGAGAGACAAAGAGGAAAAGAGAGCGAGGUAGAAAACGGAUACUGCCUAUGCCUACUCCAUCCCUCUUUCAGCACCAAGGACAGAACCUCUGAGCGGCUGACCCAAGCAACGCUCAGUUUAGGGUCCCUCCCAAAUCCUCUAAAGAAAACGGAUACAUUCGAAAGCAGCUAUGAAACAUGCACUAAGGUCUAAUAGGGAAGCUGGAAAAGCAGCACUCAAGUAAUUUCACCUUAGAGGCAAAAAUGGGUGAUUUCUUUCUGUUCAUUUCAUAGUUUCUGAGUCCUGAGAAAGGCAAAGUUUGCUUUGCUUGGGUAUGUCUGCUGUCAGUAAAUGGCUGCAGGAGCCGAAGUGGUAAACUCCUCGGUCUCCAGAAAUCAGAAGAAAAUUUUAGGGAAGCCCCUUGGCAUCACGCACCUCCCUCUGGGCUAUGGCAUCUCUGAGCCAGCUGAGUGGCCACCUGAACUACACCUGUGGGGCAGAGAACUCCACAGGUGCCAGCCAGGCCCGCCCACAUGCCUACUAUGCCCUCUCCUACUGCGCGCUCAUCCUGGCCAUCGUCUUCGGCAAUGGCCUGGUGUGCAUGGCUGUGCUGAAGGAGCGGGCCCUGCAGACUACCACCAACUACUUAGUAGUGAGCCUGGCUGUGGCAGACUUGCUGGUGGCCACCUUGGUGAUGCCCUGGGUGGUAUACCUGGAGGUGACAGGUGGAGUCUGGAAUUUCAGCCGCAUUUGCUGUGAUGUUUUUGUCACCCUGGAUGUCAUGAUGUGUACAGCCAGCAUCCUUAAUCUCUGUGCCAUCAGCAUAGACAGGUACACUGCAGUGGUCAUGCCCGUUCACUACCAGCAUGGCACGGGACAGAGCUCCUGUCGGCGCGUGGCCCUCAUGAUCACGGCCGUCUGGGUACUGGCCUUUGCUGUGUCCUGCCCUCUUCUGUUUGGCUUUAAUACCACAGGGGACCCCACUGUCUGCUCCAUCUCCAACCCUGAUUUUGUCAUCUACUCUUCAGUGGUGUCCUUCUACCUGCCCUUUGGAGUGACUGUCCUUGUCUAUGCCAGAAUCUAUGUGGUGCUGAAACAAAGGAGACGGAAAAGGAUCCUCACUCGACAGAACAGUCAGUGCAACAGUGUCAGGCCUGGCUUCCCCCAGCAAACCCUCUCUCCUGACCCGGCACAUCUGGAGCUGAAGCGUUACUACAGCAUCUGCCAGGACACUGCCUUGGGUGGACCAGGCUUCCAAGAAAGAGGAGGAGAGUUGAAAAGAGAGGAGAAGACUCGGAAUUCCCUGAGUCCCACCAUAGCGCCCAAGCUCAGCUUAGAAGUUCGAAAACUCAGCAAUGGCAGAUUAUCGACAUCUUUGAAGCUGGGGCCCCUGCAACCUCGGGGAGUGCCACUUCGGGAGAAGAAGGCAACCCAAAUGGUGGCCAUUGUGCUUGGGGCCUUCAUUGUCUGCUGGCUGCCCUUCUUCUUGACCCAUGUUCUCAAUACCCACUGCCAGACAUGCCACGUGUCCCCAGAGCUUUACAGUGCCACGACAUGGCUGGGCUACGUGAAUAGCGCCCUCAACCCUGUGAUCUAUACCACCUUCAAUAUCGAGUUCCGGAAAGCCUUCCUCAAGAUCCUGUCUUGCUGAGGGAGCAGAAGAGGGAACACUCUUUGUACCCAUUUCUAGCUGCCAGGCUGUUGGCCCACUCAGAAAGACUGUGCAGUGUCCUCCGGCAUGCAGUAGGAAGAAGAUUCCUGGAGCCAGGAUGUCCCUGCUUGUCAGGUAUAACCAGAUGUGUCCUCCAAAACAGAAUAUUCUACCUCCCCAGCUAAAAUCUGACUUCAUUCUGACAAUCUUCAAAUGACUGGGGAGCUUCCAAGUGAUAAGCAAUAAUUCAGAAAGAAGCUGAUAAAACAUGACUCACACAAAAUUGUCAUCAGAGGCAUGAUUCAUUACACUGAAGGAAAAUGAACAGAUCUCAUCAUUCUCAACUUGCAGGGGUCCUUGAAAUCAGCCAGUAAACCACCUUCUAGAACAGCCAGUCUGUCUUCCUUCAAACCUCUAAUUAACUGUCAGGCUAACCUUGUACUUUUACGGGCCCAUUCCUCUUGGUCAUUUCUUUCCUUCACUGUAUCUGGAACUGUGAAUGGCAAGGCCAGUGCUUCUACCUCUCUGUAGAAUCCGAUGGGCUACAUUUGGUGAGGUGAAUUUCUCACACCAAGAGAAACACUGUCCCACAUUGGGAUGGGGGCUUCAUUUCAAACUUUGCUACCCUUGUAUUUUAGCUUUAGCUAAGAAGGCUUUCUGAUUCCAUUCCUUUACUCUCUAGAGGAAAUCUCAGAGUCUCAACUUCCAGAAUCAUUCAAGAUGGGGAUAUUUUCUGAAGACGGAAUGACACAUCCCAUUGUAGUUUCACUGUUGAAACUUAUGGUUCAGAACAUACCUUAGAUAUGCUUUUCAUAACACUACCAAAUUUUCCUACCCAGGGCAUCUCCAUUUCUGCUUAACAGGGACCCAAUAUAGUGGACCACAUCAUGACAUUUUGGGCAACAGUGGACCACAUAUACAACGGUGGUCUCAUAAGAUAAUAAUGGAGCUGAAGAAUUUCUAUCACUUAAUGAUGUCAUAGCUGUUGCAACAUCAUAGCUCAAUGCAUUAUUUACAUGUCUGUGGUGAUGCUGGUAUAAACAAAAUGAUGCUGCCAGUCGUGUAAAAGUAUACAAUUGUGUACAGUACGUAAUACUUAAUAUUGAUAAUAAAUGACUAUGUUACUGGUUUAUGUA